AUGGAUAGGUCAGAUGUAGGAGACCCAGGGAGAGAGAGAAGGCAAGGAGCAUUCAAAAAUUGGGAAGACAGUUUGAAUAUUCAUCAGAGAGAUCCUUCCAGGGAGAUACUGAGGACGAGGACUAGAAAUAUAAGGCCAGCAGAAAUCAAGGAUGUAAAAAUCUCCCUAGAGAAGAAAAGCCAGAAAGGUAAAGAAUUUGAUAACUUCUUUAAUCUAAGCUCAAAAAGUAUUUCACAUUCGAGAAUUCACAGGGAGAAGAACAAGGGGCCAGUUUCAGAAGUCAAAAUACAAGUCACAACUUACGAAAGGCUUCAGAGUGUAGCCCCUCUGGCAGCCAGGUUUAGAGAAGCCCUAGCGGGGAAGGGAAGUGCAAAGAGGCAUCAGGGAAGCCAGGCAGGACCCAGAGCAAGGAGAAGGAAGAGAGUUUCCACAGGUGUUGCCUUCAGAGACAGGAGUGCCCUUGACAAGGAAAGAGGGCAACAAAACUACCCAGGAGAGAAACCCUUUAUCUGUAAGGAGUGUGGAAAAGCCUUUGGUCAGAGUGCAAGCCUUAUCGUGCACCAAAGAAUUCACACAGGGGAGAAACCUUUCCUAUGUAAUGAAUGCGGAAAAGGUUUCAGACAGAGAUCACACCUCAUACGACAUCAGAGGAUCCAUACUGGUGAGAAACCCUAUGAAUGCCAGGAAUGUGGGAAUACCUUCAGCCAGAGCUCAAAUCUCAUAGUUCAUCAGGGCAUCCACACUGGAGAGAAAUCUUUUGAAUGUGGUAAGUGUGGGAAAGCCUUCAGCCGGAGUUCAGGCCUCACUGUCCCUCAGAGGAUCCACACGGGGGAGAAGCCAUUUGAGUGUAAUGAAUGCGGCAAAGCUUUCAGUUGUAGUUCAUACCUUAUUGUGCAUCAGAGAAUUCACACAGGGGAGAAACCCUAUCAGUGUAAUGAGUGUGAAAGAGCCUUUGGCCAGAGCUCCCAUCUUAUUCUCCAUCAGACAACUCAUGCCCAGAAGAAACCUCAGCUGGCUACUUGGGUUAGGGCCCACUGUUAAUGGGGCAGAGUUGAAUGGUCAUGUUAUAUGCUUGCCUUCAGCCAGGCCAGCAUCUCAUAAAUACUAGGAAGUAUGUGAGAGGUCAUGGACUGUUCAUUGCUGGAAAUCUGGGUCCACAAACUCACUCUGCUUGUAUGGUGUUUUAUUCACUUGCCUUGUUUUUGUACAUGUGCCUCCAGUCAGAUUUGGAGUUCCAAGAGGUAGAUGCCAGGUCCUGUCUUCCACUUUGAUUGACAGGAAACUGAGGAGCUCUUCAUUUCUACAAAGUUGAUUAAAUUUUAAUUCAUUGAGAACUUCCUCUUAUCAAGAAACUCUUAAUCUGAUAAUCUUGCAAGAUCUCACCUGCUUUGAAGAUUUGUAAUUUUUCCAAUGUAACUCCAGCACAUUAAAGCUUACUUACUUUUCAUUGUUAUUUCAAAGCUUUAAUGUGCUAGAGUUGGGAAGCUUAGAAGGCCCACUGUGAGCAGUACUAAAAUUUAGAAUGUCACAUCCUCAUUCAAAUGUAGGCUGCCUUUAGGAGUGACCAAAACAGCGAAGGAUACAUAGGAUGAUAGAAUCAUGAAUCAAAGGAACCCUACCAGACCAGAACUGCAGACCAAAGUUAACAAGAUGAAGUAUUAAACCCUGUCCAUAGGGCUAAGGAGUCUGAGCCUCUCAGAACAGAAGUGUUCUGUCAGAAACACUGCAAUCCUUGACCAUUAGACAUGCUAGAGGGGUGUCUUUAAAAAUAUCCUUCUCUCUCAUCUUCAGUUGCUAGCUGCUCAGGGAUGAGAUCCUAGUCUUAAGGCCUGUUCUCUUCUCUCUAGACCAUAGAGCUUGACUUUUCCUUACAAGGAAAUAAAACAGAUCAUGUGUGUGUAUAAAAUUAAAAAGUAAUAUCCUAAUCAUCUGCCACUUACACAAAAAGAAAUUUAUUACCUUUAGACUAAAGGAAAAAUAUAAUAGGAAUGCAAUAUGUCUCGGUAUGUGCAGUCAUGUGCCACAUAAUUAUGUUUUGGUCAACAACAGACCACAUAUUUGAUGGUAGUCUCAUAAGGUAAUGGAGCUGAGAAAUUCCUAUGGCCUAGUGACUCUGCAGCUGUCAUAAUGUGGUAGCACAAUGCAUUACUCACAUGUUUGUGGUGAUGCUGGUGUAAAGCUGACCAUGUUGCCAGUUAUAUAAAAGGAUAGCACAUGCAGUUAUGUACAGUGCAUAAUACUUGAUAAAUAAAUGACUGUGUUACUGGUUUAUGUAUUUUACUGUGCUUUUCAUUGUUAUUUCAAAGUGUGCUCCUUCCACUUAUUUUUUCAAAGUUUACUGUAAAACAGUAUGCUGUGUUUGACCAGCAGCAGCCUCAUCUAUCUCAUGUUUACCACAUCUCUUGACUGCAUCAUUUCCUCUUGUGCUUGAUUUAAUCUCAUGUUUUGUUCAUCAUGUCUCCUAAGCAUUCAAAAUCCAUGGCUAAUUUUGCCAGUAAGAGGCCAUGCUGAGUAAUUGACCUGGAAACAAAAUUAAAAGUGAUUAAGGACUGUGAAGGUGGAAAAUCAGGGAUGGUUAUUGCUCACCAGUCAGGCAUGUCCCGUUUUACCAUAGCUGCCAUCCUAAAGAACAAGAGCAAAGUGAUAGAAGCUGUUAAAGGAUCUGCUUCAUUGAAGGCAAUGAGACUAACAAAAAUUUGAGAAGGGCCAAUAUCAGAUAUGGAUAAUAUCUGAUAUUGACCUAGAUUGAAGACCAGACACACAAGCAUGUCCCUCAGCACCAUGACAAUCACAGCUAAAGCAAAAAGCUUGUUUGUUACGUAGAUAGAAAAGGCUGGACCUGACUAUAUUGUUGAAUUUAUUGCUAGCUCUGGGUGGUUUAAAUGAUUCGAGAAUUGUUACUCAUUACACAAUUGUGAAAGUGAGUGCUAAGUCUACAAGUGCUGAUGUGAAGGCAGCUGAAUAAUUUUUGGAAACUCUAGAUAAGCUGAUUGUGGGGGAAAAUUACUUGCCAGAGCAAAUCUUUAAUAUGGAUCAAGGCUCCCUAUUCUGGAAAAAGAUGCCGGAAGGGACUGUCAUCCAUAAAGAGGCCAAGUCAGUGGCAGGUUUCACGGCUUUGAAGGACUGGCUAACAAUGUUUGGGGGCGAUGUUGCUGGCCACAAAUUAAAACCCUUUGUGAUUUGACACAGUGAGAACCCCAGGGCCUUCAAGCAUAUCAGUAAGCACACACUGCCGGUGUACUACAUGAGCAAUAACAAGUCAUGGAUGACCCAGCUUCUCUUCCAAUAUGCCCUCCUGAAUUGCUAUGCCAGUGAAAUGGAGAAGUACUGUUUGGAGAAUAACAUACCUUUCAAGAUUUUGCUUGUUGUUGAUAAUGCUCCUGUACAUCCUUUUAUUGGUGAUCUUUGUUUUAAUAUCAAACUGGUGUUUCUCCCUCUAAACAUCAACUCUUUGAUCCAACCAGUGGAUCAAGGAGUUAGAGCAGUUUUUAAGGCUCACUACCUAAAGCGGACGUUGCCCCAGGCUAUUGCUGCUAUUAUCUGAGGGAGACACUGAGAAGACACUAAUGCAAUUCUGGGAGGAUUACAGCAUCUAAGACUGCAUCAAGAACCUUGCUUAGGCUUAGGGUGAUGUCACCAAUGAGUGUAUGAAUGGCAUCUGGAAGGAGACACUCGAGGUUUGUUCAUGACUUCAGAGGAUUUGCCAUGGAUGACCAGGUUGCAAAAAUCCACAAGGCUGUGGUUGAGAUGGCAAACAGCUUUAACCUGGGUGUGAAUGAGGAUGACAUUGAGGAGCUCCUAGCGGUGGUUCCUGAGGAAUUGACUAAUGAGUUGUUGGAAAUAGAACAGGGACACAGCUGAAGAAGAGGCAAGAGAAAACAAAACUGCAGAAAACCACCAUCAAGAAAAUUUGCAGUAGGGAGUUUAGCAGAAGCUUUUGCAGACCUCAAGAAACUCCUUAAAAAGUUUGGGCCGGGCGCGGUGGCUCACUCCUGUAAUCCCAGCACUUUGGGAGGCCAUGGUGGGAAGAUCACGAGAUCAGGAGUUCAAGACCAGCCAGACCGACAUGGUGAAACUCCAUCUCUACUAAAAAUACAAAAAAAAAAAAAAAAAAGCCUGGGUGUGGUGGCACGCACCUGUAAUCCCAGCUACUAGGGAGGCUGAGGCAGGAGAAUCACUUGAACCUGGGAGGCAGAGGUUGCAGUGAGCCGAGAUCGUGCCACUGCACUCCAGCCUGGGUGACAGAGCAAGACUCAUCUCAAAAAAAAAAAAAAAAAAAAAAUUGAAAACAUGGACCCCAACACCAAAAGGUUUUCAUUAAUAGAGAGGAAUGUUCAUGGUGCAUUAUUUGUUUACUGGCAAAUCUAUGAUGAAAAAAGGAAAUACCAAGCAAACCACCAUGGACAUAUUUCUGAAAAGAGGGACACCUCCUUAAGAAGAGUCCCAGGCAGGUCCUUCAUGGGUAUUUCAGAAGAGGGCAUUGCUAUCAUAGGAGAUGACAGCUCUGUGCAUGUUACUGCCCGGGAAGACCUUCCAGUGGGACAAGAUGUGAAGGUGGAAGAUGAUGAUAUUGAUGAUUCUGACCUGUGUAUGCCUAGGCUAAUGUACUUGUGUCUUAGUUUUUAACAAAAAGUUGAAGUAAAUAAUUUAAAAGAAAAAUGCUUAUAAAAAUAAAAUAUUUUUGUAUAGCAUUACAGUGUGUGUUUUAAUCUAAGUGUUAUUACAAAAGUCAGAAAAUUUUAAAAGUUUAGUAAAAAGUUAACAUUAGGUUAACUUAUUGAAGAAAGAAAUUUUUAAGUAAAUUUAGUUUACUCUAAGUGUACAGUAUUUGUAAAGUCUACAGAAGUGUACAGUAGUAUCCUAGGCCUUCACAUUCACUCGCCACUCACUCACUGACUCAUCCAGAACAACUUCCAGUCCUGCAAACUCCAUUCAUGGUAAAUGCCCUAUAUAAGCAUACUAUUUUUUAUCUUUCAUACCAUAUUUUUACUGUACCUUUUCUAAGUUAUUUUUAGAUAUACAGAUACCAUUUUGCUACAGUUGCCUACAGUAUUCAGUACAAUAAUACACUGUACAAGUUUGUAGUCUAAGAGCAGUGGGCUGUACCACAUAGUUAGGGUGUAGUAGGGUGUAUAUCAUAUAGCCUAGGACUAUACCACAGAGCCUAGGAUGUACUUAGACUUGCCAUCUAGGUUUGUUUGAGUACACUCUAUGAUAUUCACGCAACAAUGAAAUCACCUAACAAUGCCCUUUUCAGAACUCUCCAUUGUUAAGCAGCACAGGACUGUAUUGUAAUGCUGGUUGCUGCCCACUGCUAUGAGUUUAGCCCUCCAAUUAAGUCAGGAACUGGCCCUCUCUUGGGUGUGGAUUUAUAGUCCCCAACACUAGAGGGUCAAUUUUAGAGAUUUUUAACAAACUGGAAGGUUGACUUUCAAAAUGUCUCCAGUUCCUUCUAGGUCAAUUCCAGCAUGAGAUAUACUUUAUCUUUCAAUCACUAGUAGGCAAAAAAGGGGUGCUAGGAAUCAGUCACUGGCUUGACUUCUGGCAACAAGGAAAGCCUGAGGUGAAUUACAGUUGCAACAUCUGUCAGCUCAAACUGCAUGGCGUCCGUCACAAGGAGUUGAAAUUUCAAAGUGUAAUAAUUUUUUUAAGUAUAAGAAUAAAAAAUGUCCAUCCAAAGUAUAAGAAAAUCCUUCUUACCAAAUCCCCCUUCUUUUGGCAAACACCAGGGCCCUUUUCCUUGUUAAAACAGCCUAUUUUAACAAAGGCAAGGUGUAGGGUGUGCACAGAAGCCCAGACAUUCAUGAAAGCAACUGCUAAUCUUGUGUGUUUACACAAUAAGCAUCUGAAAUGAGCUGUGUGACUCCUUGGUUUUGGUUUGCAUGAGACUUAGCAUCUGUGUGAAACUGCUAGUUGUCUUGGGCAGACACCUGGCGAAGGAUUGCAGGCCUGAAAAUGAAGGGAAGUUAAUUUUUUACUAGAACAAAAGUUCUAGUAAAAAGGGUUUUGCUUUGGACAUAAGGGCAAAGCAGAACUAAGUGGUGAAAGGACCAAAACACCUCUGCCUGAAUGGAGACGGUGGCCAGGGAAGUGACCACUGCAGCUGUGCAUGGCUCGGUGUGGGCUACAGGCGGAGUAUCAGGGAGACAGUAAAUUGAAUGGAGCGAUGUCCACCCCUGGUGUGGGCUGUGGUGUCCAGACUCAGCAGCCACUCAAUGCCCACAGCCCAGUCCCUUCUCCACUUACUGCAUACCUAUGGGCAAACUUCUUAAACUCUCUGUGCCUCACUGUCCCUGUCUAUAAAAUGGUGAUAUUAACUAUCUAAGGGAUGCAGUGAGGAUUGAGUAAAACACAUUAAGAAGAGCACUGCACAGAGUAAGUGCUUAGUAACUACUGUAUAAAAUAAAACAAUUAUUAUUAACUUGCUUUCCUGCUCUGAGACAUGGCCUAACAGUAACUUAUCUCUAGGGCAGGUCAGCAGGGGAUAACCUGUACAGCCAGAGAAACUGAAACUACCAGGUUUCUCUGGGGGUGGGUGUUGGGGGAGUCCAGGGACUGGAUGAAGUUAAUGUCUGCUGGAAGGUGGGAAGGGCCAAGGGUUUACUCUGCCACUCAUUUUAGAAGAGCUGCGCCAUUCAGGGAAGUGGCAGAGGUAGAAAUUAGAGAGUAGAGAGAUCCAUGUACUACCAGAGGCCAAGCAGCUCUGGGUAGAGACUGGUCUCUGCCCCACAGAGUUAUUCUUUGAUUCUCCACUCCUUGGCCUGCAUACUGGUUAUUCUUGUCUGCACCCCAGAUCCAUCAUCUACCUCAUUGCCCUGGGGCAGAGAUCCCUGUGGGUGGCAUCACCCUGGGUCCCUUACUUCUGGCUUCCUAGUGGGAUGCACUGGUAUGUCAGAGGGAGGCAUGAGAAUGGGACGGGGUACUUCUGUCUGCUACCAUGGUUCUGGCAGUGGCUGUGUCCCUCUGUAACCACAGCUGCAUGGCUCCAGCUACACCAUUUCCUUCCGUGCCCUUUCAAGCUAGGAGUGGCAGAGGCUCUAGUUCUUGCUGGUAUCUGGUGUCUCCCCAUCCCCUCCCCAAACCUCUGUAAAUCACCCUUUCAUUAAACUCUCUCCUUCCUGCCAGGUCCCAGCAGACUAAUAAUUGCUGGCAACUAGGGGAUCUGGAGAGCUGCACUGUAUAUUUUAUUUACUAGACCAGGCUGCAUGACAUUUUAAGCUAAGCACUGCUUAGUGAUGGGGGAAGCACAAACCUGUUCUUUAUUAACAAAACAUCCACACUGCAAAAGGAGCCAGUGCUAGGAAGGUUUUCAGACUAGCUGUACCUUACAUCUCACACAGCAUGAACAUUAGCAAGCACCCAGAGUGUCACUGGCAUGCCUUCCAUCUAUCAAGCCAAGACAGUACACUGUUCCCAACAUGCUUCAUGCUUUCCAGACAAGUCCUUCUCCUAGACACAACUCCUCUCCCAUCAGGUUUUGGGACUCCUACUCACCCUUCGAGGUUGGCUUGAAUGCCACUUUUUUCAUGAUCCACCCCAAAUCAAAGCAGCAUCCACCCUCGUCUGAACUUCCCUGCAAUUAUCCUCAGCUGUCCUCCCGCUCAGCAUGUUCUGCCUUGUGGUGGUCUUACUUCCCCUGCUGGAUUGUGUUAAGAGAAGGACCAGGUCUCAUUCCCUGUGGGCCCCUUAGUUCACCUAGCAAGGUGCCUUUUACAUAAAAGGUGCUCAGUAAAUUGCUGAAUGAAUGGACAAUGACUAAAGAGCGUCUUUGACCUACUUCAGCUGAGCAAGGUCACCUGUGGUAGGUACCAAAGUCUGAGAAGAACCAACUGGAUUUCCCCACCUGCCUCCCACGUGGUCUCCCUUGUCUCCUUUUCCUCCUCUUUGUCCGUCUACCCUGAGUUCCCAUCAGCUUCAUUCUCCCAACACUUCCCUCCUCCGUCUAUUAGUCCUCAUUCUGACAAUGGCUUCAAAGCUCUGAAAUCACAAGUGGCAGAGAGAAGAGAGCUCAAAGCCCCUCAUGUCCAACUCCUGUCCUGCACAGGUGUGGAAAAUGAUGCUCAGUGGCUUGCCCAGGGUUAACCUGGUACACGAAGCCCAGUACCGUGGGCAGGGCUUGGCCUUGGUUGGUACCACCCACACACCGGGGCUUUUGUCCUGAAACUUCUCACCUCCCCAUGUGCCUGUCAAGCCUGCCACUCCUAGUGACUGUACAGCCAGUCUCUCCCCUCACUGGGGCCCACCUGGAGGCAUUCCUUGUUUGCUUAGUCCCCUCCCUGGGCUGUCCCUCAUCCACCUACUGCCAACCCAUUCUCCCAGAGCUGGCCCACUAAAGCUUCACCCAUUUCCCCUCCCUGCUGAUCUUGCUAUCUCUGCACACAAUUCAGCACUUUAAUCUCAGCUUGUCACCUACUGUCCUUUACUCAUUUGUGUGUUUACUGUGUAUGUAUCUUGUCUCUCCAAAGACACCAGGAGGCCCUUACAGGAGCCUACCUUAGCCUGAGAGCUAGGUUGGUGACAAGGGCUCAGCUUGCUCUCAUGUGGAUUCAGUGCUGGACCUGAAGCCCUGACCCAUCAGCACUGGGCUCUGACCGGGGAAGUUGGCUGGUAUUUCUUCCAGGCAUGCUCCCAGGUACCAGGCACUAGGCAACCAUGAGGGGCCCUUCAGGACAUGCUCUGCCUCUGACUGGUUGGGUCAUCUCAGAUGAUUUGCAAAACUCUGAGUUGAUUUCCUCACCCUGGAAAGGUGGGAGCCCUGGCCGAAGGCCUUUCCAUACUGGGUGCAGCAAUAGGGCUUCUCCCCCGUGUUGCUCUACCAGUGAACCAGGAAGCACGAGCUGCAGCUGAAGGUCUUGCCACCCUAUGGGCACAUGUGUGGCUUCCACCCUGUGUGCACGACUAGGCUUGGUCCCUGACUGAAGGCCUUGCCACAUGUGCCACAGACAAAGGGCUUCUUCCCCAUGUGUACCCUCUGGGGCUAGGUCAGGUGGGAGCUCUGCAUGAAGGCCUUGCCACACUACCCACACCCACACGGCUUCUCCCAGGUGUGGAUUAUCUGAUGCACGAUGAAAGUGGAGCUCUGGCUGAAGGCCUUGCCAUACACAGUAUAUGCUUAAGAGAUUCCUGCUAGGGGCAGCCAGGCUGGAGUUGUGGCAGACCUCUUUCCUGAGUUCCUUAUAGUUCCGGCCCCUCUCUCCUGGGAGACCUCUUUUCUUUUGUUGGGGCCUGCCUGGUGUCUGGCUUGUCUCUCCUCACUUGCUUGUCUGCAGGCUGUUCCGAAUGCCCUGUUCCCCUACUUCCCACUUUUCAUGCUUCCAGUCUUCCAGAGAAUUCUCCUUUCACAUUUGUUUUUUCCGGAAUCAAAUCUGCCUUUUCAACUUUGGUCUUGAUAUCUAAACAAGACAUAGAAGAUAACAGAUAUAACAAAAGCAAAUAAAAAUAGAAUCAGCUUUAUAUUCUAGAUGGGAAACAUGAAACUAUAGUGGGAUUUGAGGGAAUUCAAUAAGUAACACCCUUCUCUUCAGAGGCAAUAUAGCAUUGAGACCAGGGGUGUGGUCUCUGGGGCCAGACUGUCUGAGACCAAAUCCUGUCUUUGCCAUGAACAGUUAUGUGACCUUUCUGUACCUCAGUUUCCUACCUGUAAAAUGGAUUAAUACUAGUACCUAUGUCAUAGUGAUGUUGUAAGAAUUAAAUAAGUCAAUGCACAUGUACAAUGUACAUGAGUCAAAUACAAUGUACAUGAAGUGUUUAGCUAGGUAUUAGCUAUUAUUAUAAUUUUAUACUCAAUAUUCGAACCAACUGAGAAAUAAUAUGGGGAGACCAACAUAUCACUUUUAUUAGUGAAAGCCUGAUAUUGGUGAAUGUGGCUGUAUCUGCAGGCAAGUGGGGUUAUGAAUCCCAGGAUUAGGCAGCAUUAGCCACCCAAGGACAUAGUGCUGGCUGCCAUGGGUUUGCUCCUGAAACACCUGCAGCACAAACGGCCAGGAUGGAAUGCAUGGUUUCUGUGAAGAUGCCAGACCCCAAGGGAGAAGUGGGAGGAGGACUGGCUUUCCAAAACUCACCAGUCAAAUAAAAUCCCUUUUUGUAGUGUGGCAAGAGUGUGUGAGGAUCAGAGUAAGGCCCCAAGUGUUACACCAGUGAGCUUCCUGAAAUAUCUGGGAUAGGAAGCACAGUACUUACAAUCAUAAUUGUCCUGUAUGUAUACUAUGGUUUCAGAGCAUGGGUAGAGAAAAAGAAAAGAAAGAGUAGUCAAAACAAAACAAAACAACAACAAAAAAAUGCAUUCUGGGAAAGAGCCAGGGAUGGCACUGUCACCAAACAUUUGUCUGAUGAGGGCAAUGCCUGCAUGCAUAAAGACUGCCAAGCUGAGAGGAGGAGACAGAGGCGACUUGGAAACUGGCCAAGGCAGCAAGUGGUGGUCAGAGAUGGGCUGGGCUGUGGACAUGGCGUCCUGGGAGUCACAGAGCUUGACCAAGUCAACUUCCUGGCUGGAGAGAGGCAGGAUGAGAACUUGUGACUCAAGAGAGAAUUCAGAGAUCUAUCAGAUAAAGUGGGGAAAGGGAGAACAAGGGUACUGCACAGAGGGAAGGGUGUUGAGGGCUGCCAGGUUUGGCAGUAGGGGAGGCAGAGAGAUGUGGCUCCCUAGCCUCACAAUCCGCGAGCUCAGUCCAGGCAGGAAGAGAAAGCACAAAGAAGCAGGGCAAGCCAACCCUCUGAAGUGUGGGGAGGGACACAUGCAGGGCCCUUUCCUCCCCCUAAGCUACAGGAAAUACAGCAGGAAAGAAGGACGCUGUUCUAGGAGGUCCAGGAGGAGCAGCUCAGGCUUUUGCUUCCAGGAGGCCUGAAGAAACAGAGGAGUGUGGAAAUGCUAAAUAGCAGAGCACUGUCCCAAGGGCAGAGAUGGCCAUGGUCCACUCUAGGCCCUAGCCCUCCAGUUAAGAUCUUGAUAUGAUUUGGCUAUGUCUCCACCCAAAUCUCAUCUUGAAUUGUAACUCCCACAAUUUCCAUGUGACA